AGACGCGGAGCCAUGGCCGAGGUGUUGCGGACGCUGGCCGGAAAACCAAAAUGCCACGCACUUCGACCUAUGAUCCUUUUCCUAAUAAUGCUUGUCUUGGUCUUGUUUGGUUACGGGGUCCUAAGCCCCAGAAGUCUAAUGCCAGGAAGCCUGGAACGGGGGUUCUGCAUGGCUGUUAGGGAACCUGACCAUCUGCAGCGCGUCUCGUUGCCAAGGAUGGUCUACCCCCAGCCAAAGGUGCUGACACCGUGUAGGAAGGAUGUCCUCGUGGUGACCCCUUGGCUGGCUCCCAUUGUCUGGGAGGGCACAUUCAACAUCGACAUCCUCAACGAGCAGUUCAGGCUCCAGAACACCACCAUUGGGUUAACUGUGUUUGCCAUCAAGAAAUACGUGGCUUUCCUGAAGCUGUUCCUGGAGACGGCGGAGAAGCACUUCAUGGUGGGCCACCGUGUCCACUACUAUGUCUUCACCGACCAGCUGGCCGCGGUGCCCCGCGUGACGCUGGGGACCGGUCGGCAGCUGUCAGUGCUGGAGGUGCGCGCCUACAAGCGCUGGCAGGACGUGUCCAUGCGCCGCAUGGAGAUGAUCAGUGACUUCUGCGAGCGGCGCUUCCUCAGCGAGGUGGAUUACCUGGUGUGCGUGGACGUGGACAUGGAGUUCCGCGACCACGUGGGCGUGGAGAUCCUGACUCCGCUGUUCGGCACCCUGCACCCCGGCUUCUACGGAAGCAGCCGGGAGGCCUUCACCUACGAGCGCCGGCCCCAGUCCCAGGCCUACAUCCCCAAGGACGAGGGCGAUUUCUACUACCUGGGGGGGUUCUUCGGGGGGUCGGUGCAAGAGGUGCAGCGGCUCACCAGGGCCUGCCACCAGGCCAUGAUGGUCGACCAGGCCAACGGCAUCGAGGCCGUGUGGCACGACGAGAGCCACCUGAACAAGUACCUGCUGCGCCACAAACCCACCAAGGUGCUCUCCCCCGAGUACUUGUGGGACCAGCAGCUGCUGGGCUGGCCCGCCGUCCUGAGGAAGCUGAGGUUCACUGCGGUGCCCAAGAACCACCAGGCGGUCCGGAACCCGUGAGCGGCUGCCAGGGGCUCUGGGAGGGCUGCCGGCAGCCCCGUCCCCCUCCCGCCCUUGGUUUUAGCAGAACGGGUAAACUCUGUUUCCUUUGUCCGUCCUGUUGUGAGUAACUGAAGCCUAGGCCCCGUCCCCACCUCAAAUCACACACACCCCCUCCCCACCACAGAGACACCAUUACAUACACAGACACACACAGAAAGACACACACAGACACAAAAUCACACACACACCCUCCCCGCCACAGAGACACCAUUACAUACACAGACACACACAGAAAGACACAGACACAAAAUCACACACACACCCUCCCCGCCACAGAGACACACCAUUACAUACACAGACACGCAAUCGCAGAUACGCCCUUCCGGCCACAGAAACACACCAUUACACACACAUACACAGAAAGACACACACAGACACACAAUCACACGCAGCCCCUCCCCGCCACAGAGACACACCAUUACAUACACAGACACACACAGAAAGACACACACAGACACAAAAUCACACACACACCCUCCCCGCCACAGAGACACACCAUUACAUACACAGACACACACAGACACACAAUCACACACAGCCCCUCCCCGCCACAGAGACACACCAUUACAUACACAGACACACACAGACACACAAUCACAGAUACCCCCUCCCGGCCAUAGAGACACACCGUUACACACACAUACACAGAAAGACACACACAGCCCCUCCCUGCCACAGAGACACACCAUUACAUACACAGACACACACAGACAUACACAGACACACACACAGACACACAAUCACACACAUCCCCUCCCCGCCACAGAGACACACCAUUACACACACAGACACACACAGAAAGACACACAUACACACAAUCACACACACCCUCUUCUUGCCACAGAGACGCACCAUUACAUACACAGACACAGACACACAGAGACACAGACACACAAACAUAGACACACACACACAGACACACACCAGACACGCAAAGACACACAGACACAGAUACACAGAUACAAAGACACAGACAUAUAGACACACAGACAUGCACAGAGACACAUGGAGACACAUGCAAAAAUGCACAGAGAAAGACAUACAGAAGUGUACACACAGACACAUAGACCACACAGACACACAGACAUGCAUGCAAACACACAGACAUGCAGACAUGCACACAAACACAGACUCACGCACACAGACUUAGGCAGCCCAAAUUCAGCGCCUGGGGCAUAAGUUCCUGGAGGGGUGGCCACCUUCAGCCCCCACGGUAAGGUCCUGAGGAACCUUCCCCUUAGACAAGGGAUCAUGGAGGAGGUCUCUUCCGGAGCCUGGAGGGAGGCCUCAAGUGGUCCUUCCACCUCGGCAUCCCAAAGUGCUAGGAUUAUAAGCAUGAGCCACUGCACCUGGCCCCAACAUCAUUUAUUGAACAGACUGUCGUUUCCACAUUGUGUUUCUUGGCAUUUCUGUCAAAAAUCAGUUGACCGUAAAUGCAUGGAUUCACUUCCGGGCUCUCUAUUCUGUUUCAUUGGUCUGUUUGUUUUUAUGCCAAUACCAUGAUGUUUUGAUUAUUAUAGCUUUAUAGUAUAUCUUGAAGUUAGGUAGUGUAUUGUCUCCAGCUUUGUUCUUUUUGCUUAAGAUUGCUUUGGCUAUUUAGGGGUCUUUGUGGCCAUUACUGACAGUUAAAAUGGCCCUGGCUCAUGUCUCCUGGGCCUCUACAGUACUUUAGGUGGGGAAGUACUGUGGCCCACAUGUCCCAACAGGCUGUGUGUGGCACCUGACAGUGCUUUGUGCCACUGUGGAGCAGGUGUUACUCCCUCAUACGAAUUUUAGGAUUAUUUUAUUUAUUUCAGUGAAAAAUGUCAAUGAAAUUUUGAUAGGGAUUGCAUUGAAUCUGUAGAUUGUUUGGGGUUGUAUGGACAUUUUAACAAUAUUAAUUCUUCCAAUUCAUGAACAUGGGAUGUCUUUUUUUUGGCACCUGAUCUCAGAUAUGGGACAGCUUUCUAAUUAUUUGUAUCUUCAAUUUCUUUCACAAAUGUUUUAUAGUUUUCAGCAUACAGAUCUUUCACUUCCUUGGUUGGAUUUAUUUGCAAGUAUUUUUUGUAGCUAUUGUAAAUGACAUUGUUUUCUUGAUUUCUUUGUUAGGGUAUAGAAAUGCUACAGAUUGUUGUAUGUUAAUUUUAUAUCCUGCAACUUUACUGAUUUCAUUUAUUCUAACAUCUUAUUGGUGGAAUCUUUAGGGUUUUCUAUAAGAUCAUGUCAUCUGUAAACAGGGACAAUUUAAGUUCUUCCUUUCCAAUUUGGAUACCUUUUAUUUCUUCCUCUUGCCUAAUUAUUUUGGCUGAGGGCCAACUUGUUGGGUUUGUUGUUGUUGGUUUUUGUCUGUGUCUUUUGGUGUUUCGUGUUGCUGGCUUUUCCAGCACACAGUCACAGAUAUAUGAGGCAGAAAGAAAACCCAGGGAACUCCUGUCAUGUCAUUCCUCAGGUCCCAAGGUCCCUACAUGGUCUGCCUUCUUCUCUCCACCUUUUAGUGUUUGAUAUACAUACGUUUAUGUAUGUAGUUAUAUAUGUAUGUGUAAUACCCGGGGAAAUAUACAGAGAUUUUAACUGUCCUUAGUGUAGGGCGUGGGGACAGGUGCAUCUAUUCUACCUUGCCUGGAAGUGGAAAAAUCUUCAAGAAAUCAAUUUAUCACCAACUGGCAUGACAGAACUCCUGGUUUAGUGUCUAGCUGUCUCCACUAAAAUCAAUCACCAUGCCAUCAGGCACUCUCUUCCCUCUGGUGUGUACUGGUACCUGAAACAGCGUCCAGCACCCUGAGAGCACAGAACGCAGCUUCUUAUGUGCCCCACCCAAUAAUCCCAAAUCGAGCACAGACCUGGGAGCUGAAGAGACAAGCUGGAGGUCAGGCAGUUCUAUUACUUAAGCCUGGUUCUUCCUGACUCCAAAAGCCAGGCGCCACCCCAUGCUCCUUCCCAGCAGAAGCUGGUUUUCACCGGGUCAGGAGGACAGGAUGGCUAUUCCUGACCGUUGUACAGCAGUGCCACAUCUCCUAGUUUCCAGAACAUUUAAUGUGUUGCUGUGGAGGCCUGGCAGCUCUGAAGUAGCCCCUUGCGCCCAGGACAAACCGGGCCUGGAGGGGUGGGGUGGGGUAAGCUGAAGCUUCCAGUAUCCCACGUGGGCAUUCUGUUGCUGAGGGCAACCGCCCCUCCCUGCAAGGGAGGGGAAGGAGCAGGCAGGCACACCCUUCCUCCCUCCACAUUUCACUGGAGUUGACCUGUGUCCUACUGUGGUUGCACCUGGACCAGCCCAGAGGGACUGGAGUGACUCUUCCCGCAGGUAGGGCACAGCCAGCCUGGGCACAGGGCCUCACUGCAAUCCCUGCGCCCCGCCUCCCUGGGGGAUUUCCAGGGGUUGUCCUGCUGCUUGGUGAGCUGGGGGUGUGGGGGACCACAGAUGAGGCAGGCGCCUAAAUUGCUUGGGCGGAGUCCGGCUGCUCUCUCCCUCCAGGCCCUUUCCUGUGUCCUCGGGCCCCUCGGGUCCCUGCACCAGGCCAGCAGCAAUCGGGUGUCAGAGGUUCAAGUCCAGGCUGACUCCUGGGAUGCACCGACUUUGCCCAGGAGGGCUGGGGAGAGGGCAGCCCCAAAGUGUCAUCUUUGAUUAUUCUUUGUCCCCAAAGCCAGCCUUGGGCAUGUGCCCAGCACAGGGAGAGCUGCUGCCUCUGUGGGCUUGAGUCAUUUUUGCUUCCUUGCCCCUCUCUGCUCUGUUUGGUUUAAAAAACAAAAACCAACACCCAUGGGUGAGGCGAGGCGAGGCGAGGCUUGCCUUGAUCCACCCGCUUCCUCCCCUGCAGCCUCGGGCCCCAUCCUCCCGCGUGGCCGCACUAGGGGUGCUGGGGGCGGAGUGGGGACCAGACCUGAGUGGGUUCUGGGUUCGGCUUCGCAGCAGGAGCAGCUGGGGCAUCAUCAGUUGGGCAGGUGACCCAGGAUCUGAGCAGGAAUCUUCCAGGUGGAGGUGGGGCCGCCCCUCUGCUUGCCACAGCUGCCUUCUGCUCUGGGGGCAGCACUGGCUGAGAAUCCAGUGAAGUAAGGCCUUUGAAAUGGUUUUGAUUGUAAAAGUAAUGUUUAUGUUUAGCCAUUCCUUUUUUUAUUUUUUAUUUUUUGAGACGGGUCUCCCUCUGUCACCCAGGCUGGAGUGCAGUCGUGAAAUGUGGGCUCACUGCAACCUCCACCUCCCAGGUUCAAGUGAUUCUCCUGCCUCAGCCUCCUGAGUAGUUGGGAUUACAAGUGCCUGCCACCACACCUGACUAAGUUUUGUAUUUUUUAGUAGAGAUGGAGUUUCACCAUGUUGGCCAGGCUGGUCUCAAACUCAUAUCCUCAAGUGAUCCACCCUCCUCGUCCUCCCAAAGUGCUGGGAUUUUGCCAUGAGCCACCACGCUCAGCCAUGUUUAGCCAUUUUUAAAAGGUGUGAACAGAUAAUUAAGUCUAUUAGCAACAUUAGAAAAUUUAAGUUAAAAUUUAAAUGACUCUAGCAAGAAUUAGCCUUUAGGUGCCCUGGGUCCCCCUCCCCACCGCCCCCCACCCCGCCGCCUUCUGAGAAGCGUUUUGUAAUUUUUCUUAUUUAUAAAAUGGGUUUGAUUCAAAACUGACUUUUCCUCUUCACAGAGUCUCACAGGUCCUUCCCCAGGUCCAAGAGGCUCUUCUGUGGUCUAAUGACAAGUAGCUGCCUAGCCGUGGUGGCACCUCCUAUCACAUGUUAAGGGACCCCUCCCCAGGGCCACACCUGGCAGAAGGUGGCUUAUGAUGUUCGCAGCUUGAAAGUAGUGUAAACCAAAGAUAAAAUUCUAAGCCCACUCCCCCAGCCAUCGGAAUGGACCCCUCCUCUUGGCCAGGGCACUCCAAAGUUAACCUGAAAAACCGGUUCAGGCUGUGAAGAGAAGGUGGAGUGGACAUGCCUCAUUUAUGUCCUCCUCCCUUUUGGAAUUCAGCAAAGCUGACCAGCAUGAACAUUAACACAGACCUUAAGUCUGAUUAGUGGCAUUUACAAUCUAUACUCUCUGAAGCGUGCUACCUGGAGGCUUCCUUUGCAUGAUAAAACUUUGGUCUCCACAACCCCUUAUCAUAACCUAGACACUCCUUUCUAGUGAUAAUAACUCUUUCAACCAAUUGCCAAUAAAAAAAUUUUGAAUCUACCUAUAACCUGGAACCUCCCUGCUCCACCUUCGAGUUGUCCUACCUUUCUGGACAGAAGCAAUGUGGAUCUUGCAUGUAUUUGAUUGAUGUCUCAUGUCUCCCUAAAAUGUAUACAAUUAGGCUGUGCCCAGAUCACCCUGGGCACAUGUUCUCAGGCCCUCCUGAGGUCUCUGUCUCGGGCCAUUGGUCACUCAGAUUCGGCUCAGAAUAAAUCUCUUCAAAUAUU